ACAUGGCAAGACCUUGUCUCUAAAAAAAAAAAUUUUUUUAAGGAAAAAAUAAUAUAAUUCAGGAGGCCACGGGAUUUGGGAAAGAAAGCAGACUGUGACAAGAGCAUCUAACUGUAUUACAAAUAUAUGAAACAACCUCACCGAAGGGAUGGGGAGAAAAGUGCUACCCUAACUUUGAAAAUGACUGGAGUCUGUAAAACUAAAGGCCAAAGGAACUGUACAAGAGUACUUACUCAAGUUGAUAAAGUUUUUCUGCAUGGGUUUAUAGGUUAAUAAAUGCAUUGUUGCUAUACUUGUAUACUAACAUUGAACAAUAAGAAAAUAGAUAGCAGAUAGUGGGAGCCAGGUUUCUCACUGUUGGAGUGGAAAUUUUAUGUACACUAACAUUGACCAAGAAGAAAAUAGAUAGCAGAUAGUGGGAGCCAGGUUUUUCACUGUUGGAGUGAAAAUUUUACAAAUCAACAAGGGAGGAAGCUAGAAUGACCCAUGUGGUAAUGGAUUAACGUUGAGGAUACUAGAACAGCUCAUAUAUAGUUAGAUAGUUGCUUGUGGAAAUUUUUAUAGAUGGGUAUGUGCACAAGUUAGUAUACAUACUAUAAAGUUUAGAAGUUUACAACACCACCACCACUUCUGACUCCAAUUGUAAGUUUAGGGGUCCCCAAGAUCACCCUCAUGUUGAAUAAUUCCCUAGAGGUACUCACAGAACUCACUGAAAGCUGCUAUAUUUACAGUUAUGGUUUAUUACAAUAAAAGGAUACAUAUUAAAACCAGCCAAGGGAAGAAGCACAUGGGACAGAGUACAGGAGAAUUCCUCAUGUGAAGCUUCCAGUUUCUUCUCCUGCUGGACUAAUGGACAGUGGUAACUUCCCCCAGCAACAAUCUGUGACGACACGCUAGAAGUAUUGCCAACCAGUAAUUGCCCUUCCUUUUUGGCUGCUGCUUUAGCCAGAGCCACAUCAGAUGAAGUCCUUCAGAGUGAUCUUUCUGCACAUUAUAUCCCAAAGGAAACGGAUGGCACAGAAGGGACUGUGGAGAUUGAGACAGUGAAAUUGGCCCGUUCUGUCUUCAGCAAACUACACGAGAUUUGCUGCAGCUGGGUGAAAGACUUCCCCCUCCGCAGGAGACCCCAGCUUUAUUAUGAGACAUCAAUCCAUGCCAUCAAAAACAUGCGCAGGAAAAUGGAGGACAAACAUGUCUGCAUUCCUGACUUUAAUAUGCUCUUCAACCUAGAGGACCAGGAAGAACAAGCUUACUUUGCAGUGUUUGAUGGCCAUGGGGGAGUAGAUGCUGCUAUUUAUGCCUCCAUUCACCUCCACGUUAACUUAGUCCGCCAGGAGAUGUUCCCCCAUGAUCCUGCUGAGGCCCUGUGCAGGGCCUUCCGGGUCACUGAUGAGCGGUUUGUGCAGAAAGCAGCCAGGGAGAGCUUAAGAUGUGGGACCACAGGAGUGGUGACUUUCAUCAGAGGCAACAUGCUACAUGUGGCCUGGGUGGGUGAUUCCCAGGUUAUGCUUGUGAGAAAGGGCCAAGCUGUUGAACUAAUGAAGCCACACAAACCAGACAGAGAGGAUGAAAAGCAGAGAAUUGAGGCCCUUGGAGGUUGCGUAGUCUGGUUUGGUGCCUGGAGGGUGAAUGGAAGUCUGUCGGUUUCCAGAGCUAUUGGAGAUGCUGAACAUAAGCCAUAUAUCUGUGGGGAUGCAGAUUCUGCCUCCACUGUUCUGGAUGGGACCGAAGACUACCUCAUUCUGGCCUGUGAUGGCUUCUAUGACACCGUGAACCCUGAUGAGGCAGUGAAAGUUGUGUCCGACCACCUGAAAGAGAAUAAUGGAGACAGCAGCAUGGUUGCCCACAAAUUAGUGGCAUCAGCUCGUGAUGCUGGGUCAAGUGAUAACAUCACGGUUAUUGUGGUAUUCCUGAGGGACAUGAACAAAGCUGUAAAUGUUAGUGAGGAAUCAGAUUGGACAGAGAACUCUUUUCAAGGAGGGCAAGAAGAUGGUGGGGAUGAUAAGGAGAAUCAUGGAGAGUGCAAACGCCCUUGGCCUCAGCACCAGUGCUCAGCACCAGCCGACCUAGGCUAUGAUGGGCGUGUGGAUUCAUUCACUGAUAGAACUAGCCUGAGCCCAGGGUCCCAAAUCAACGUGCUGGAAGACCCAGGCUACCUAGAUCUCACACAAAUAGAAGCAAGCAAACCUCACAGUGCCCAGUUUUUGCUACCAGUUGAGAUGUUUGGUCCUGGUGCACCAAAGAAAGCAAAUCUUAUUAAUGAGUUAAUGAUGGAGAAAAAAUCAGUUCAGUCAUCAUUGCCUGAAUGGAGUGGUGCUGGAGAGUUUCCCACUGCUUUCAAUUUGGGUUCAACAGGGGAGCAGAUAUACAGAAUGCAGAGCUUGUCUCCUGUCUGUUCAGGGUUGGAAAAUGAACAGUUCAAAUCCCCGGGAAACAGAGUUUCUAGAUUGUCUCAUUUACGCCACCACUACUCAAAGAAGUGGCACAGAUUCAGGUUUAAUCCAAAGUUUUAUUCAUUUCUCUCUGCUCAAGAGCCUUCCCACAAAAUAGGCACUAGCCUGUCCUCACUUACUGGAAGUGGGAAGAGAAAUAGGAUAAGAAGUUCUCUGCCAUGGAGGCAAAAUAGUUGGAAAGGGUACAGUGAAAACAUGAGGAAGCUCAGAAAGACUCAUGAUAUUCCAUGCCCAGAUCUUCCUUGGAGCUAUAAAAUAGAAUAAUUUUUCUUUCAAGUAGGUUAGCUAGCUCUCCCCCAAUAAAAAUACCACUAUCAGAGUAGAAACAAGGUAGACAUUUCUAAAACAUAUGUGCUUCAUUAUGAAUCCAUGGAUGGCUCAAUUCUUAAAUGUAAAUAGAUCUCUAGGAAACUCAAAGUACAGUGUUUUCAAUCUAAAAAGAAGUAUUGGCAGUUUCACUUGCAAAAUUACACAGCUGGUCCCUGUGAUGUGUCUCGACACCAAUACACAACCCCCUUCCCACCAUCCUUCAUGUCACUAGAUACACAACCCCCUUCCCACCAUCCCUUCAGUCACUAGUGGAAGCUUUCAAGUUAGUUAUUUCAGUCAGGAUAUACAGUGUUGAAAUCUCAAUGCAGUUGAAAUCUGGUCUGAUGUGCCUAAUUUAUCUGUGGAAAAUUUAAUGCUGAAUUACAUUUGGUUGGGAAAUGUCCCUCAAAAUCCUGGGCACUAUGAAGGAACCCCCUGCCCCCUCACCUUUUUGGGUAGGUAAAAGACUAAAAGCCAUAUGGAUUUUAACUGAUAACAAUGAAAGUGGUAAAUCAGUGUAAAAGUGUCAUAUUCUCAGACUUGUGAGGCGGUUUAUAGUCAGAAAGAUUUACGGAUUUUUUUCCUGUAACAUAAAAGAUUGUGAACUUUUUUUAAUUAAAAAAUAUUUCCUAGGGCUGUAGUUAUUUGGGAGUUUCAUAACCUGUUAUGGUGCUUUUGGUGGAAAUUUUUAUUAUUUAGCAUUUUAGGAGACCGCUGUCAACUGGUUUUAAUCUAUGAUGCUAAUGUGUUUUCCACUGUACCCUCAUCUCAGGAAUAAAACUGCUUUAACGGAGAUGAUGUCAGGUACAAAUACACUAUAGAGUCAAAAUACCAUUUACAAAGAAAAUCAAAAGCAUUUCUAUAUUUUGUCUUUUUUUAGUUCAGACAGCAAAGGCAUGUACUACUAUAAAAUACAAAGUGAUUUUAGAGAAUGAAAAAUGCUACUUUUAUCUUCUCUAAAAUUAUUUCCCCCAAGGUAGUGAAGUAAUUGGAAUGAAGGAGGCUGAAAGUAUUGUCUAAAGUGAGCCCAGAGGCCACUGAGAAUGCAGAUUACUGACAGCCAGGUCUGUUUAGUUGUAAUUGGAAGACACAUGAGUGUCCUGCUUACAUGUAGCUUCAGACUGCAGAGACAGGACGUGUGCUUUUCAUUUCAAUAUUUAGUUAUAUUUGAUAUUUUGAAACUGUCUGCUUUUUGCUAUUUCUGCAGUUUCAAGUUAGUUAGAAGCAUGUUGUCAACUAAAGACAACAAACUAUCAGAUUCAUUCAUUCAGUGAAGCAGCCUCUGAUUCUCUAAGAGUCACGAAUGUCUUAGUGUUACCCUCCCCUAGUCAACAGCAGACCAGCCUGGCCAAUGCCUAUGGGUGGCCCCUCUGGAGUGCUCACUAACAAGGGUGAGUGCUCUCGCUAAGAAGUGUCCCCCGCCUAAUCAUGUGUUUAUAGGAUAGUACACGUUCCCCAGGCCCAUAACAGAGGACUAAAAUCUCUGAAUUUUAAAGACACAGAUGACUGGCAUAUUUUGGAUACCAGUAUAGCUAUAUCAAAUAGACAAAAACAGCUUCACUUUAGCAAUGAUCAGAUUGUUAAUCUACAGAUUUUAUUUUUUAAAAUUUGGAUGUAAGUAGAGACUUUCAGUAUUUGUUUUCUCUUGAUUUUGAAGUCAUUUCUUCUUCUCACGUCUGUGACAAAUGGUUGAAAAGGAGUCAACAUGGCCCCAACUAUAGUGCCGGAACCUUUUCAUCAUUCUGAGGCUUUGCCCCACACAUGGUCCUCACUCAUAUCUGUCACCUUCUGAAGCCUAGAUCUUGUUAACCCAUCAGGUGCAGUGUCAGUUUCAAAUCAAAUUAUCUAAGAAAACAAGAAAACAAAGGCAGCAGACUAUUGGUACACAUUAUAGUCCAAAGUGCUUAGCGAAGUAAAAAAAAAAGCUUUUUAAAAUUUCUAUUGUUGUCUAUUGGUAAUGUUUUUGAUCAGAAUAAAGAGGGUAAAGGGAAAAAGUUACUACACAUGCUAGGCUUUCUCAGUGGGGAAAAAAAUGGCUGGAUAGAACUGGGACAAACACAGACCCAUCUUUAGGGGUCUGGAUUUUGUAGGUCCGACUACACAGCAGUGUUAACUCAUUUCUCAUGCCAUUAGCUCUCUACAAAAUAAAGCAAAGUAGUUCUAGUGUGGUCGUUAUAAACCAAUAUUGUGAAAAAUAGCAACUAUUCAUUUGUUCACAACAUGCGUAUUUAUAGAGUAGUUAGGUACCAUUUGUAAGGUAAAUCCUUUAAAAUUCUAUAAUACAUACUAAAAUAGUGGUUAUUGGUCUGAUAUAUGCUGCUCUUGGUUCUAUAAACUAGAUAAAAGCAGUGCUUUGUGAAAUGCAGUGUUCUCUCUUAACGCCACUGGUGAUAGGAAGUAGUUCCCUUCAGUUCAAAUCCUGUGCCCUUAUUUGCUGCUUGCUGACGUAAGCAAUAAGUAACCCUCUAACUAAUGGUAUCUACAUAUUUCUGUAACUUGUAUUUAAUGAUGGUGUACCUGGUGAUUGUAAAAAUAUUAGACAGAUAUAAAAGUAUCUAUAUAAUAUCUAUAAACUGUUAAUGCUGAGGUAUAGUCUGUGAAUUAUGUGUUUUGUAUUUUUAUUCAUUGUGUAAUUUAGUGGUGGUGAAAGUUCUACACUCAAUCCUUAAAGAGUGGCAGUAUCCCUUUUUCAAUUUAACAUGGUCUGCAUCAAUCUGUUUGCCUGCUAAACAAGUUAGAAUAGGAAAUAGUAAAAUAAAUCCAAACAAGAGUGUAAUAUUGGUUAGGGAAACAAACUUCAGGUCACCAACUGAAGUCAUUACAAACUCCUUGUACAUUCACUGUGAGUUUCAAAGGGAGUCAGUCCCUAAUUUACAGGUUUCCUUUGUUCACUUUCUAGAUGUGUACUUUUGAGGGACAUGAGGUUAGGCAACAUUACAGCAACACACACUGGGGCUAUUAAUCCCAUUUAGGUCUGUACUAAAGAGGAUGGGUAGAAACACAUAUGUAUAUACCUUUUCUUUACCUAGAAGUGCCAUCCAUUGUCCUUGAAUUAUUAUGAUUAAAGUUACUGUUGCAUUUAGGAGGCUCCUUGAAAGUAACACCUUUUCCAAGGACAAUGGCAACAAUGUCAAUGUCAACACUGAGUCUAAUUUUGACCACAUUUAUAGUGGUAUAGUGUCAAUACUGCAUUUUCAUGACAACCACACUCCACUGUUGAAACACUGUGCCAGUGAGAAGUGCAACAUCCAGUGGGCAGAUGAAAAUGAUGCAUGGCCAAGUUCAGUGUUUACAGAUAAAACUGCUGUGGUUCAAGUGCUUCCUUCCCCAUCAAAUCCUUGAUAAGGCUUUGUGGGAAAAUGAUCUAAAUUAUUGUUUUAAUUUUUAAACCUAAUUUAUUCACUCAGUGAACAUUCUUACCUAAGCAAGGCUAUAAAAGGGAAUACUACAGUUUUGUCCACACUUUAAUUUGAGACCAUUUUUCUUUGAAUCGUAAGUUAGCAAAAGAAAUUUUUUUCACCUUUGAAAAUCACGUGAUGUUAAAGGACAAAUGCCCACUCUUCUAUUCUGAUCUGCAAAUAGCUUAAAUGUCUCUUGCAAAACAAAGUAAGAUACCACCAGUAUUACAACACAAUGAUUUUCCAGACAAAUGGUAUGGUGUUGAAAAAUAACUGUUACUUCUUAAAGCAGCAUUUUAUCUUCUAUUUUGAAGACUAUUUAUUGUAAUAAUUAGAAAACAUGAAAUAGGGAACUCCAGACUGACACAGCAGUUGUUUUUGAAAAGGAAAUAAACUUUGAUGAAUUAGAUAAUCCAGAUACAUCAUUGUAAACUCUUACUCUAGGUGCUCUUUGGUGAGAGACAGGCUUUGUUCUCUUGUUCAUAACAUUUCUCUGCAAAGAAUUCUCUAUGGAGUGAAGCGAAUGAAGUGAAUAAUUUCUUACCAAAUAAAUUUAUCAAUUUACAAAUCUGCUCUACAUCUCACUUUUGAGUUCAGUUGUAGUCAUGAGUGAUCCUUCAUAUUUUAUUAAAAGUGUUCAUUCAGGUAAGGUGUAUGUUGAAAUUUUGCCAAUUAUCUUAAUAAAACCUGGCAAUUUAAAAACCA